AGACCUGCGACUGGCCCAGUCGCCCCUGGGGCCCUUUGCCACUCCCUUGGCAAGGAGAGCCGAGACCUCAGUUCCCGGCGGCUCUUGCGGGGCACAGGUGAGCCCUGGCUGCGCGCGCGGCCCCUCCUCCCCGGCGCCUCCCAGGUGAGCGGCCGCGAUCCCGGUCCCGGGUCCCGCCAGCCCCAGCUGCUUCUCCUAUGCGGGGACAGCGGCAAUCCCCCCUGAAUUCCUUUCGGCCUCUGGGGCCAUUUGGCAGCCGAGUUCCCUCCCCGGGUGCUCCUGGAGCUCCCAGGGCUUGACCCUCCGGCUCGGACAGAGCUGGGAGCGGCAGGGGCGGGGAGGACAGUGCGGGGAGCAAAAUCCGCAGCCCCCACCCAGGUCCCCCAGCCGAGCGCCAGGGCACGGGGAGGGGAGGGGAGGGGGUGUGGCCGGGAUGGGAAGGGGCGGGGGACAGGGAGGCCGGCUGGACGGGUUCGGUGGCCCCAGAGUUGCAGCCGCUCUGGGCUCUGGGGCCAGGUUGCGGUUCUCCCUGGGUAGCGGCUGCUCCCGGGAAGCUCGCUGCCGGCUGGGGUGGGGGUUCCUGGAAACGGGCGCCACCCAGCCUCUCCCCACCUAGCUCAGGAAUGGUGCGCCUGGAAACUCCGCUGGACUUGCCUGGGCCUCGGGGCGGAGUGCUGGGGCGCUGGGUGCCCGAGUCCCCGGGUUCCCUGAGCUUAGAAGGGCCUGUCUGGAGGAAGGGAUUCCAGCUCUAGGGACUGGGUGGGGCGUCCUCAGCCCCUCUUUCGGCAGCUGUCCCGUGUUAGGCUGGGUGGGGCCGCCUCGGACCCAGCUCUGGGCUGGUUUUCCCACGUCUUUGCUCCUGCUGGAGGGAGGGGGUGGUGUGGGGCCUGGGCCCGAAGAUGGCACCCAGGACACUGAGGGAGGGCGCCGUCCGGUCCUGUGACUGGCACCCCUGCAAGGAGCUGCUCUGUCGGGGCGCCCCCGGGCUUUGCCUGUCCGAGGAAAGCGCCCUUCAACCCGGCCGACUUUGAGCCCUGAGUUCCUGAGGGUGAGCGCAGGAGGAGUCCAGGGCAGAGGCCGGCAGGACUCGCUGGUGGCUGGGAGCUGAGUCCUGGCUCCACUCUCACAGAUGAACGGGCCCCGAGCCCAGGGCCCCAGACAAGGCUGCUCUGGUUCCAGUUGUGCCGGGUGACGGCAGAGCCAGGACAAAGGAGGCCUGUUGAGGUCCUGGCCACCCCCAGCCGGCCGCCCUGGGAUGAUGGAAUGCAGGGCAGUGGGUCUUCUGAGAACAUGAGGACCUUGGCGCCCUGACGGCGGUGGCAUGGAGUGACCUCUGUGUGUGGGGGAGGAGCCCCCUGUGCUGCUUCCGCCUGGGGCUGGUUGGGGGUGAGGGCUCCAGCAGCUAAUUUCCUGCUAGAGGAAGUUCUUUGAGGUCACAGGGCAGACGCAGAGAAGGCCUACAGCCUACUCUGACCUUUCUCUCCAAAAAGGAGGUGUCUCUGUGCCAGAACCCUGGGCAUGGAGAUCCUGAAAGGGGCUGUGUCUACAGGCACCCUACCUCUUCCCCAUUUCCCAGGGACUGGCGACAUCGAGGAAACAGAUGUGGAACUGCAGACCCCACACCCUUCCUUCCUCUCUCCCCUCCCCUGACACUGGAGGGGGCCCCCCAUUCCAUUCUGGCAUGAGGCUUAUUCGGUGCCUCACCAUUUAUGUACCUGGGGUGAUAGGGGGGUGGGCGGGACUGUCUGGGCUGUGAGUGGCACCUCCUGUGGUUCCCCCAGGAAUGGGUGGUGUGGACAGCUGCCAGGCGUUGAAGACCACCCCUGGCUCUGUGCCCCUGUCUCAUCAGAUGGGGGCUCCGGAGGUGGCGCCCAGGCUCUGAGCUACCCUAGGUCUGCAGACUAGCGGGCAUUGGCCAGAGACAUGGCCCAGCCACUGGCCUUCAUCCUCGAUGUCCCUGAGACCCCAGGGGACCAGGGCCAGGGCCCCAGCCCCUAUGAUGAAAGCGAAGUGCACGACUCCUUCCAGCAGCUCAUCCAGGAGCAGAGCCAGUGCACGGCCCAGGAGGGGCUGGAGCUGCAGCAGAGAGAGCGGGAGGUGACAGGAAGUAGCCAGCAGACACUCUGGCGGCCCGAGGGCACCCAGAGCACGGCCACACUCCGCAUCCUGGCCAGCAUGCCCAGCCGCACCAUUGGCCGCAGCCGAGGUGCCAUCAUCUCCCAGUACUACAACCGCACGGUGCAGCUUCGGUGCAGGAGCAGCCGGCCCCUGCUCGGGAACUUUGUCCGCUCCGCCUGGCCCAGCCUCCGCCUGUACGACCUGGAGCUGGACCCCACGGCCCUGGAGGAGGAGGAGAAGCAGAGCCUCCUGGUGAAGGAGCUCCAGAGCCUGGCAGUGGCACAGCGGGACCACAUGCUUCGCGGGAUGCCCUUAAGCCUGGCUGAGAAACGCAGCCUGCGAGAGAAGAGCAGGACCCCGAGGGGGAAGUGGAGGGGCCAGCCGGGCAGCGGCGGGGUCUGCUCCUGCUGUGGCCGGCUCAGAUAUGCCUGCGUGCUGACCCUGCUGGCUUUCAAUGCCCUCCUGCUGCUGCUGCUGGUGGCCUUCAUCAUGGGCCCUCAGGUCGCCUUCCCACCCGCCCUGCCGGGCCCUGCCCCCGUCUGCACAGGCCUGGAGCUCCUCACAGGCGCGGGUUGCUUCACCCACACCGUCAUGUACUACGGCCACUACAGUAACGCCACGCUGAACCAGCCGUGUGGCAGCCCCCUGGAUGGCAGCCAGUGCACACCCAGGGUGGGUGGCCUGCCCUACAACAUGCCCCUGGCCUACCUCUCCACUGUGGGCGUGAGCUUCUUUAUCACCUGCAUCACCCUGGUGUACAGCAUGGCUCACUCUUUCGGGGAGAGCUACCGGGUGGGCAGCACCUCUGGCAUCCACGCCAUCACCGUCUUCUGCUCCUGGGACUACAAGGUGACGCAGAAGCGGGCCUCCCGCCUCCAGCAGGACAAUAUUCGCACCCGGCUGAAGGAGCUGCUGGCCGAGUGGCAGCUGCGGCACAGCCCCAGGAGCGUGUGCGGGAGGCUGCGGCAGGCGGCUGUGCUGGGGCUUGUGUGGCUGCUGUGUCUGGGGACCGCGCUGGGCUGCGCCGUGGCCGUCCACGUCUUCUCGGAGUUCAUGAUCCAGAGUCCAGAGGCUGCUGGCCAGGAGGCUGUGCUGCUGGUCCUGCCCCUGGUGGUUGGCCUCCUCAACCUGGGGGCCCCCUACCUGUGCCGUGUCCUGGCCGCCCUGGAGCCGCAUGACUCCCCGGUACUGGAGGUGUACGUGGCCAUCUGCAGGAACCUCAUCCUCAAGCUGGCCAUCCUGGGGACACUGUGCUACCACUGGCUGGGCCGCAGGGUGGGCGUCCUGCAGGGCCAGUGCUGGGAGGAUUUUGUGGGCCAGGAGCUGUACCGGUUCCUGGUGAUGGACUUCGUCCUCAUGUUGCUGGACACGCUUUUUGGGGAACUGGUGUGGAGGAUUAUCUCCGAGAAGAAGCUGAAGAGGAGGCGGAAGCCGGAGUUUGACAUUGCCCGGAAUGUCCUGGAGCUGAUUUAUGGGCAGACUCUGACCUGGCUGGGGGUGCUCUUCUCGCCCCUCCUCCCCGCCGUGCAGAUCAUCAAGCUGCUGCUCGUCUUCUAUGUCAAGAAGACCAGCCUUCUGGCCAACUGCCAGGCGCCGCGCCGGCCCUGGCUGGCCUCACACAUGAGCACCGUCUUCCUCACGCUGCUCUGCUUCCCCGCCUUCCUGGGCGCCGCUGUCUUCCUCUGCUACGCCGUCUGGCAGGUGAAGCCCUCGAGCACCUGCGGCCCCUUCCGGACCCUGGACACCAUGUACGAGGCCGGCAGGGUGUGGGUGCGCCACCUGGAGGCGGCAGGCCCCAGGGUCUCCUGGCUGCCCUGGGUGCACCGGUACCUGAUGGAAAACACCUUCUUUGUCUUCCUGGUGUCAGCCCUGCUGCUGGCCGUGAUCUACCUCAACAUCCAGGUGGUGCGGGGCCAGCGCAAGGUCAUCUGCCUGCUCAAGGAGCAGAUCAGCAAUGAGGGUGAGGACAAAAUCUUCUUAAUCAACAAGCUUCACUCCAUCUACGAGAGGAAGGAGAGGGAGGAGAGGAGCAGGGUUGGGACAACCGAGGAGGCUGCGGCACCCCCUGCCCUGCUCACAGAUGAACAGGAUGCCUAGGGGGACGGCGAUGGGCCUCACGGGCCCGCCCAGCACCCUGAGACCACACUGUUGCCUCCCAGUGACCCUGCUGGGACACCAGGACAAGGAAGACAGUUUCGCCUCUCGAAAGCCGCAGCUGCGCCUAGGCUGGAGCUGGAAGGGUGGGUGAAUCCGGCUUGGGCAUCCCCAAUGAACUCUGCCCUGCCUGGGACUCUAUUUAUUCUGAUUAAAGGGGUUUUGCAAAUGGGCUUGUCCCUUGGGGCUCUGUGUCUGUGACCACACCCGGGGCCUGCUUCCCGCUGCCCUGGGGCCACCUCCAGGCGCAGGUCUGGGUCCUGGGAACCUCAGCUGGAGUGGGGGCGCCCUCUGCUGGCCAAGCCCCAGAUGGCAGGGGCUGGACCGCGCCAGGGCUUGAUUCGCUUGCUGCCUUUGACCAGCCUGAACUCGCGCCCAGGAGGGGCUUACACCUGCACAAGUGAGCCGAGCAGGCACGGAUUGUGACCAGAGCGAUGCGUCAACCAUUGGGUGAUGCUGUAGCAUCUACUGGAGCAGGAGACAAAUUUAGAGAGGGACUUGGAGGGGAGACAUAUCAGUUGCAAAUGAGUUGUGGGGACAGUUGCCUCCCAGGCAUAGGUAACCAGCACCUGUGCUUGGAGGCGAACAGGGCUUGGUGAGGUGGGGCUGGCCCCCUGCUUCUGGCUGCCAGCAGCUGGCUGGGGGGUGGUGAUCCUGGGUCUGACUGGGCUGAGUUUGAGGAGCCCGUGGGAUACCGAAAACCGUAGGCUGUGGGGGGUGGGCACAGGGAUUCGGGGACCAGCCCGUCAUGACCCCGUGCUCCAGGUCUGCAGGGACCAGCCCAUGACAGCCCAGGGCUCCAGGUCUGCGGGGACCAGCCCAUCACAGCCCAGGGCUCCAGGCCUGCGGGGACCAGCCCGUCAGCCUCAGUUCUCCAGGCCUGCGGGGACCAGCCCGUCAUGACCCCAGUGCUCCAGGUCUGUGGGGACCAGCCCGUCAGCCUGUGCUCCAGGCCUGCAGGAACCAGCCCGUCAGCCUCAGUGCUCCAGGCCUGCGGGGACCAGCCCGUCAGCCUGUGCUCCAGGCCUGCGGGGACCAGCCCGUCAUGACCCCAGUGCUCCAGGUCUGUGGGGACCAGCCCGUCAGCCUGUGCUCCAGGCCUGCGGGAACCAGCCCGUCAUGACCCCAGUGCUCCAGGCCUGCGGGGACCAGCCCGUCAUGACCCCAGUGCUCCAGGUCUGUGGGGACCAGCCCGUCACGGCGCAGGGUUCCAGGCUUGUGGGGACCAGCCUGUCACAGCCCAGGGCUCCAGGCCUGCAGGAGCUGCGCUUGGGAUUGGGGGAAUGAACCCAGGUGGGGAAAUGGUCAAAGAGCGAUGGGCCCAGAAAAGGGUCAGACCCAGAUGGAGAUGCCACUGGCUGCUAGCAGACCCCCACGCUGGGUCUAGCCCACCCAAUCCCAUGGGGAUGCUCCUGUGCUCUGCAGACAUCUGGGUGCUGCCACAGGGGCCCGACAGAGUUGGCAUCUGGGUGGAUCUGAGCCAAGUGGUGCUUCUGGGCCUCAGCAAGUAGCUGGUGCUGAUUCUGGGCAGCCAACUGUGGCAGCAUCUUCAGGUGCGAGUGCUGCUGGGUGAAGCUGCGUGGGCAGUCCAGAAAGUGACGUGACAGUCCACAGGGACCGACGUAGGGUUUCCAGCCCCUAUCUGUGCAGAUGCUGUCCUCCAAACCAUCACGGUCCCUCUCUGGCUGGGGACGUGCGCCUGCCACUGCUGGCUUGCCAGCAUGAUCAUUGGUUGUGACCUGUUGAGCCCAUCUUGCCAGCCUCACAAAGGACAGUACUAGCUGCUUAUGACAGGAAAGUGGAAGAACUUGGCCUGGAUAUUUCUGGAGAAUUACCGUGUGUGCUAGUCAGUCUUUCGUGUCAACCAGGCCAGGCUGUGGGGCCCAGUGAUCUCAUCGAGAGGGGCCGAGGUGUUGCUGUGAUCGUGUGCUGCUGGAAUGUGGUGAACACCUACAGUCGAUUUCACCUAAAGAUCAUCCUUGAGAAUGUGGGUGGGCCUCAUCCUAUCAGCUGAAAGCUUUAAGAGCAAAACCCGAGGUGUCCCAGAGAGGGAAUUCUGCCUUGAGACGGCGGCUUCCCACUCCCACUGGAUGUCCAGCCCGCGGCCCCACGGCUGGGUGAGCCCGUCCUCUCCUCGUUUCUGUCUCCGGACCCACCGUGUGGCCCCAGACCCUCCAGUGAGGACCUCCCGUAUUUCUUCAGAGCAGCCCUUGCGUGCUGGAGGCCUGGGCUUCAGUGUGUCCCUGGGUGCCCUGGGGCAUGUUCUGUGACCUCCCAGCUCCUCGCCUCAUGGGGCCGCUGUAUCAAGUGACACAGUUUGUGUGCUGCGUACCAUGCCUGGCACCCAUUUGAGGUGUUGCAAGGAGGCCAUGUUUGCUCGAUGAGAGCAGCCUAAGAUCUACAAACUGUUGUUCGAGUGGAUGGGAACUUGAUGCUAUUUUCAGGCUGAAUGACAAGACUCCGCGAUGCUUCUCGGCCUGGGCUGCACAACGGAAUCUACCAGGGAGGUUUUAAAAACACUGGUACUUGCUGGAGGUGGUGGCGCCUGUCUGUAAUUGCAGCUGCUCCAGAGGCUGAGGCGGAGGAUUGCUUGAGCCCAAGAGUUUCGGUUUAUUUGCUUUUUCAGAGUCUUGCUCUUGCCCAGGCUGGAGUGCAGUUCCAUGAUCUCGGCUCACUGCCUCAGCCUCCCAAGUAGCUGGGAUUACAGGUGCAUACAACCAGGCCUGGCUGAUCUUCGUAUUUUUAGUAGAGAUGGGGUUUCACCAUGAUGGUCAGGCUGGUCAAGAUCUCCUGACCUCAAGUGAUCUGCCCGCCUCGGCCUCCCAAAGUGCUGGGAUUACAGACAUGAACCACAACACCUGCCGAGCCCAGGUGUUUUGAAUCCAGCACGGGCAAUGGCAAGACCCUGUCCCAACAAACAAAAAAACACUGGUGCCUGAGGCCCACCCCGAGAGAUUCUGAUUGAGUUGAUUUGGAUUUGAAUUAUCUUUAAAAUUUUGGAUGUGAAUUUUUUUUUUUUUUCUUGGAAUGGAGUUUCACUCUUGUUCCCCAGGCUGGAGUGCAACGGGACGAUCUUGGCUCACCGCAACCUCCGCCUACUGGGUUCAAGCCAUUCUCCUGCCUCAGCUUCCCAAGUAGCUGGGAUUACAGGCAUGUGCUACCAUGCCCAGCUAAUUUUGUAUUUUUAGUAGAGACAGGGUUUCUCCAUGUUGCUCAGGCUGGUCUUGAACUCCUGACCUCAGGUGAUCCGCCCGCCUCGGACUCCCAAAGUGCUGGGAUUACAGGCAUGAGCCACCAUGCCUGGCCGGAUGUGAAUUAUCUUAAAAAUUUUCAGGUAAUUCUAAUGGGCCAAGGUUGAGAACCCCUGCUCUGGGCCCAUCCGAGCACCAGGCUGUCACAAACGCAUGCAUGCACUCACGCCCGUGGGCUUGGGGGGCUUCGGAAAUGUGCUUCUGCUUUUUUGAGAUGGGGUCUUUCUGUUGCCCAUCCCGGAGCACAGUGGCACGAUCACAGCUCACUGCAGCCUCGACCUCCUGGGCUCAGGUGAUCCUCCCGCCUCAGCCUCCUGAGUGUCUGCUUCUGGUUUUCAUGAUGACCUGGGGCCCAGGCAUACUACACUUGUGCUGUUCAGGGGCCAGUCCUGCACCAGGAGCCCAUCAGCCACAGCUCCGCCGAGAAGCACUGAUAUGCAGAGCUAAGCAGCUUUGUUUCCACGUGGAUCCUGCGUAGGUUUUCUUGGUCCAUCCGUAGACACCGCACUCCUGCAGAGGAUCUUCUCGGGAUGCCCCACUGUCUCUGUUUUCCCUCUUCACUGAACACUCAGUCGGGGCUCGCCAUGAUGCCUCUGUGUCUGCUGGCUUCUCCCCCAUUGGAACAGCCUUCUUGGCACGCCACACUGCUAGCUGCUGGGCACUGUGCUUUCUGCCUUUACCGUUCUGCCGUGAUGUUGCCAAAAUAGCAGCAACAACAACAACAACAAAGGCUGGGCACCUGGCUCAUGCCUGUAUUCCCAGCAGUUCGAGAUCAGCCUGGGCAACAUGCCCCAACUGGACCCUAGGCAAAAGUGAGUGGCACUCCUCUGCCAGGACUCCAGGCAAGCCCCGGCAUCUUCUUGCUGCCGUCCCAGACAACAGAAGUUACCAGAUGAACAGACUUGGAUGGGCCACGGGGGUGGAGAGCUGGAAAGCUUGGCUGUGCCUCUCGAUGAUGAUUAAGAUUUCAAUAUUUACAGCAAAACCACAAAGCAAAUGAUAGAAUAAAGCAAAACAAUGGAAAAUCUGAGUUCACUCGUGAGAGAGGUACGUAUGUGAGCUCUGAGGAAAUUACAGAGGGAACGCAUGCAGCGGGACAGCUCUCCCAAUCGCAGCGUGCAAAGUAGACAUCCAUAGUGUCUUUUGAAAAAUGAAAAACACAUUACUUUGAACAGCCAAGAAAAAAAUUGCAAUUUAUUAAGAUUCAAUAAAGCGUUGUACUUUCGAAAGCAA